CCUGCUUUUGGUUCUUACAGUAGUCGGCGUAGGCCUUAGGUGGGUUCGUGCGCCUUCUACCUCGCUGUUUCGGUUUUCCUGGCUCCUCGGCCCUUUUCUCCCCUGUUGCAGCUGGGAGCGGACGAAGCGCGAAGCUGGGAUUUUUUACUGUCUCCUGAAGAAUUUAACACAAACAUGGAUAUCAGACCAAAUCAUACAAUUUAUAUCAACAAUAUGAAUGACAAAAUUAAAAAGGAAGAAUUGAAGAGAUCCCUAUAUGCCCUGUUUUCUCAGUUUGGUCAUGUGGUGGACAUUGUGGCUUUAAAGACCAUGAAGAUGAGGGGGCAGGCCUUUGUCAUAUUUAAGGAACUGGGCUCAUCCACAAAUGCCUUGAGACAGCUACAAGGAUUUCCAUUUUAUGGUAAACCAAUGCGAAUACAGUAUGCAAAAACAGAUUCGGAUAUAAUAUCAAAAAUGCGUGGAACUUUUGCUGACAAAGAAAAGAAAAAAGAAAAGAAAAAAGCCAAAACUGUGGAACAGACUGCAACAACCACAAACAAAAAGCCUGGCCAGGGAACUCCAAAUUCAGCUAAUACCCAAGGAAAUUCAACACCAAAUCCUCAGGUCCCUGAUUACCCUCCAAACUAUAUUUUAUUCCUUAAUAACUUACCAGAAGAGACUAAUGAGAUGAUGUUAUCCAUGCUGUUUAAUCAGUUCCCUGGCUUCAAGGAAGUACGUCUGGUACCAGGGAGGCAUGACAUUGCUUUUGUUGAAUUUGAAAAUGAUGGGCAGGCUGGAGCUGCCAGGGAUGCUUUACAGGGAUUUAAGAUCACACCGUCCCAUGCUAUGAAGAUCACCUAUGCCAAGAAAUAACAUUUGGGAUAGUCGUCUUUAAAAGACUUGGUGUUAUUUACAGUGUUUGUUUUGAUAACAUUUGGCUGGGUCAUUUUAAUAGUUAGAGAUGAGGAGGAGUAAAAGUGAAAUUUUUGUGAAGGACUUAAAUUAUCCAGUGUUUCUUUAGCCUUGGUGAACUAUGAAAUACGAAGGCCUUAAUUUUGUACAAUAAACUUUUAUUUGUAUUCUGUGUAUAUAAUGCUUUCUUGAUUGACCCAUCUCCCUAUCAUCAAAUGACUUCUAGUCUAGAACACACUUAAGGUUUAUAAACUUGUGUAAUAGGAUGCUUUUCUAGUGUUACUUUGGAGGAGCUAAUUAUACAACAUCAUUGAACCAUUCAAUAAAAGUUAAGUAAAAUUAGAUCACAGAAGCUAGUAGAUGACUGUUGUAUUAAUGGUAACAAUGAUUGUUCUGGGUAUUAGAAGAAAAUGAGACCCAGGCAGGAUCUAAAUUUGAUCUUUGUAUCCUUUUAAGAAAUGAAUAUAUUAUUUUGCUGCUAGUAGGGAUUCCACAAGUUUUCUUCAUUCAGUAUUAAAUAAAGGCUGUUCUUACUGUUUACUGAGAAAACAGAAAGGGAAUGCUAUCUUCACACUUUGCAUUUAAUGCUGUUUCCUUCAUGAGGCAGGACUGUUCUAAGGUUAAUAUGCAAUCUCUUUAUUGAAAGACCUCCAGGGUAAAAAUUUUUUGAUCUAUAGUCUCUUUUCCCCCUUAAGACAAAUAGACUGAUUAAUAAAGAGUUGCCAGUGCUAAGCUUGCUACUUCUUUGUAAUUCUUAAACACCAAUGUUCAAAUAUUUCCAAAGCCCAUUUUCUUUAGCUUUUGAUUUAUGUUUAAGGCUAUUGAUUCAGUCCUCUGCUGAGUAAACCAUGGGUAUCUCCAGAAGUGGACAAUUUGUUUUUACAAGUAUGGUACAUAUUAAUAGUAACAACAACAAAAAAGAAAACAGUACUUAUUUUUCUGGUGUUCCUGUUUUAGUAUUCCUUGAACAAAACCUUUAUCACUUGGAAUUUUUAUUGUCUACUUAUGGAAAGACUUUUAGACUUACGUAGACAGUAUCACAUCACUCUUAUGCAUACAUAAAGAGGAAAAAAAUGUUUCCUAUAACUUUGUCACAGUUAGUCUGACUCUUCUGAAUAACUUUUUUAAUCCCAGUAGUCAAGCUCCUGUACUUUUGUAAAAUAUAUUAACAGUGAAUUACUAGAAAAUGGGCCAUGUUCUUGUAUAUUACAGUGAUGUCAAUUGCUGAUAAAUUUUCUAACUGCUUACUCUCGGAUACCGUACUUGUCUAAGAACUGAAAAUAAUUCACAGACUGAUCCCAUGCCCAGUCCUGGCCAUGCUUUGAGUGGCUGUAUUGGAGCAGAAAAGCCAGGGUGGCUCACCUGGGGUGAGAAUGAGGGGGGUGAAUAGUAAGAGGGGUCGUGUAGGUCUUCUUCAGGAUUUGCUUAUACUCUGAGUGAAAUGGGGGACUAUUUUAGAGAAUUUUUUUAAAGUGGGUUAGAAUUUACGUACAAUAAAGUUCACCCAUGUUAGUGUUCCA